GCACUCAUUUGCCCAAGACGAUAACUCACAAAACGCCCUGUGGCCCGACUGUCACGACUGUAGUUCGCCAACCAAGGGCAUUUCCUGGAAAUGCAAGGGGACACGUAUCUGUGACACUAAUGGCCGUUCUGACGUGCGUUACGCCCCUGGAAGGACUUGGAAAUACUGAACUUGAGUGAGCACUGGGAGGAUGGAGACCCUCAUCCUGGGAGGAGUCACUCCUCCCGCAGCCAUCACAGCCUGACGCCCCCUCUCCCCAGAAGUGCUUCUUAGGCCCACCCAAAAGGGCAAUGGACCUCUCUGUAUGCAAGCCAGAGCAGUCUACUGUUUGUGUAUAUUUGGGUUGUUUACUUUCUUUUUAACACUUAAAUGUUAAUUGACUUCAAUCAUUUUUAAAAUUAUAAAUAGUGUCGCUAUAGACUUUUUUGUACUUAUUAAGUACUGACCUGCAUGAUCUUCGUGAAGCAGUGCUUCUGUUACCAGAAAGGGGUCCGGAUCCGACCCCAAGAGAGAGUUCUUAGAGCUCACGCAAGAAAAAAUCCAUGGGAGAGCACAGUGCAAAGCCAAAGCAAGUGUAUUAAGAAAGUAAAGAAACAAUGGGUACUCCAUUGUUAGAGCAGCAGCUUGGGCUGCUGGACUAGGGAUACUUGUAUUUAUUGCUUGAUGAUGUGCUAAACAAGGGUGGAUUAUUCAUGAGUUUUCCAGGAAAGAGGUGGGCAAUUUCAAUUUCUCGGAGCUGAGGGCUUCCCAGCUUUUUGAACCAUACAGGGUAACUUCUGAACCUUACCAUGGCAUUUGUAAAUUGCCAUGGCACUGAUGAGCGUUUCUCUUAGCGUGCUAAUGCAUAUAAUUAGCAUAUAACCGAGAGGUGAAGCCAGCUGGGCUUCUGGAUCAGGUGGGGCCUUGGAGAACUUUUCUGUAUAGCUGAAGGAUUGUAAAUACACCAAUCAGUGCUCUGUGUCUAGCUAAAGGUUUGUAAAUGCACCAGUCAGCACUCUGUAAAAACGGACCAAACAGCACUCUGUAAAAUAGACCAAUCAGCGCUCUGUAAAAUGGACAAAUCAGCAGGAUGUGGGCGGGGCCAAAUAAGGGAAUAAAAACGGGCCACCCGAACAACCAGCGGCAACCGCGCUGGGGUCUACUUCCCAGGUGUGGGAUGUUUGUUCUUUUGCUCUUUGGGUCUGCACUACCUUUAUGAGCUGCAACACUCACCCUGAAGGUCUGCAGCUUCACUCUUGAAGCCAGCGAGACCACAAACCCACUGGGAGGAACGAACAACUCCAGACACGCCGUCUUUAGGAGCUGUAACACUCACUGUGAAGGUCUGCAGCUUCACUCCUGAAGCCAGCGAAAUCAUGAACCCACCGGGAGGAACAAACAACUCCAGCACGACUCCAGACGCACCGCCUUUAUGAGCUGUAACACACACCGCGAGGGUCUGCAGCUUCACUCCUGAAGCCAGCCAGACCAGGAACCCACCAGAAGGAACCAAUUCCGGACACAUAACAAGCAGCAGUGAGGACACCAAAGACACAGACCCAGAUGCAGAGGCAGAGGCAGCCACACAGCCCCUCCCAGCCACAAUCACAACCUCAUAUUCAUAUAAUCACAGACCCUCCACCCCACAUAGUGGGUGGAAUCCUGCCAGCGCAUUCCACUCACACACACACAAAAUCCCAUUCUCACACACGUGCACCCAAGCCUCGUCCCGCACACACAACAUGACAGGCCACAGAGCCGGCUGAGAGUCUCAGCACGCAUGGACGCCUGCACUGCGCAGGUUGCAGCCCAGGCUGCAGGACCACAGGUGGCAGGGACGACACAGCAGGUGGCCGGCCAGGGAGUGGCAGUGGCCUCCAUCCUCCCUGCUCAGCCACAGCCCCUGCUUCAGCGUCUGCCAGUCCAACUGUCAACUCAUCCACUCAACUUUACAACUGGAAUGUGGGGGCGUUCAGGGCCCUGCCACUGGUGACGGCCACUCUAAGUCCUACCCAAUGCUGGGUAGGUCCUUUAAGAGGCCCAAGUCCUGGGCGCUACUAUGAGGUUCUGUACGUGCACAGUGAUGGCUCAUGCCUGGCCGAGGUGAGCCCACUCAGUCUGGGUGGCACAGCCUAAUCUAGGAACUGCUCUGCGGUUCUACAUGGCUCUCAGCAGCCCAGUGAGUGUCCUCUGCACCGGGCGUGUCCCUCAGGUGCUCCUAGCCAGACCCUCCCUUGACACAGUAGGGCACAAACCGCUAUUGGAGCGGCACUGGCACCCGAGUGUACAAGCGUCAGCAUCCCUGCUGCCUUCCCCACCCCCAGCUGUCCCCACCUGCUGAUUCUGCCCCUGGGGUCACACUUACAAUUUAGGGUCCUGUCAGGAGACAAAAAUCACGUGAGUGACAUCAGCUCCCUCAUAUGUAGGUGCUGGGAAAAGGGCUUGUGGGGUGCCUGUAUAAACUGGCCAUAAAAAUACGGGAAUAAGUUGUGGAAAGCCACAAAAGGCCUCUGAGGAGGAAAGCCUCCUAAUUGCCAUCAUGUUCCCAUGCUCAGAGCAAGACCCGCUGUCUUCUCUGUAAACACUGUGCUCAGGGAGAAAGACACUUCUUUGAAACACUGGAAUGUGGACAGACGUGCAGGCUCCCAGUCAAGGCCGCUCCUACUAGCUACUCUCCAACAAGUUAAAGUUAUGCUGUUUGAGCACAAAGGAGACUCAUUUAAACUGCUAUUGCUAUAGAUUAUGCCUGUGAUGCACUGCCACCCUUUCACUGUUUCUCCCUGAACAUCUGCUUCUUAGAUCGAAGGGACUGUACUCAAUAAAUAGUGUGGAGACCAGAGCUCGGCACCUUUUGCAGCCUCCACAUUUUGCACUGGCCCCCUGGCUCCCCACCUUUCACUCUUAACUUGUCUUUUCUCAAUCCUUUGUCACCACCAGACUUCGGGUACCCUACGGGUAGUGUUGAGGCUGGUCCCCAACAUGUAGGAUCCCUUCACUGUGUCACAUGUGUCCCUAACACACUUGCUACAUCUCAUGUCCUUUAGGUUCUGUGUUUUACUCCAGAUAAUGUUCUUUGAAUCUAAAUUACAGUUUACUGAUUUCUCAAAAGCUGCACCUAAUGUGCUAUCCAUUCAGACAGACAUACUCACUUAGCAAAUGUUUGUUGAGCCAGCACUCAGUGGCAGAUUCUGUGCUAGGGCGUGCCAAGUGCAGACACACGUUUGCCAAGACACAGGGUCACAUGUGCAUGCACACUCAGACUUGCAGGCUUACACCAGUGUUCAGCCUGCUCCCAAUCCCAGGGAGCUCCAGGGAGGACAGAGAGAAUGUCACAACACCCAACCCCUCCCACUGCAUGCUGAGUCCAGUUCCCGAUACGCUGCCACCCCAACAGCAUGGCCCAGGGCCGAGGGUCUCUCUGCAGACCUGCCCUGACCACAUUCACACACACACACACACACACACACACACACACACACACACACACACACACGAAGAGGCAUGUGCCUUGUUCAGAUAUACAUAAAGCUCACCCAUCGCCAAAUUCCCUGCCUGUGCCUGCUGGGACCAGACUCCGCUGUCAUGAGGGUGACAUCCGCCACCUGUGCUCUUCUGCUGGCUCUGAUCUGCAGCGUCCAGCUGGGGGAUGCCUGCCUGGAUAUCGAUAAACUGCUUGCGAAUGUUGUGUUUGAUGUGUCCCAAGACCUCCUGAAGGAGGAGCUUGCUCGUUACAACCCCAGUCCCCUGACAGAGGAGUCCUUCCUCAAUGUCCAGCAAUGCUUUGCCAAUGUCUCCGUGACAGAAAGAUUUGCUCAUUCAGUUGUUAUUAAGAAGAUCCUUCAGAGCAACGAUUGCAUAGAAGCAGCCUUCUGAUCUGAGGACCCCUGCAGAUCAGAUAUUGGCCCUCCUGCCUUCCUUGGGGCUCCCCGCGUUCCUGGCCUGGCUCUGUUCAUCACUACAGAGACCCCAAUGAACACCUGCAGCUCAGUUCUGUGUUCUGGCAUCUGUGUGGGGUUGGCUGUGACCGCAUAUGCAGAGUGUGACCAGGGUCCCAGUGUGAAAAUAUGCGACUGAGGAAAAACUCUACAGGUGUAGCAUAGACAUGCCUGUUUUCUUUUUGGCGGGGAGGAGGGUGGCUGGAGUGCAUUGGCGCGAUCUUGGCUCACUGCAGCCUCCACCUUCUGGGUUCAAGCGAUUCUCCUGCCUCUGCCUCCUGAGUAGCAGAAUACAGCCACACACCACCACGCUUGGCUAAUUUUUGUAUUUUUAGUGGAGACAGGGUUUUGCCAUGUUGGCCAGGCUGGUCUCAAACUCCUGACCGCAAAUGAUCCACCUACCUCAACCUCCAACGUGCUAGGGUUAGAGGCAUGAGCCACUGUGUCCAGUCGAUAUGCCUGUUUUCGGAACCCAGGAAAUCAACCUUAACACACUUCUCCAUCCCUACCUACCCAAGCUGUCCUUUUUUCUCCCCCUACCUCUACCCCACAACCCCUCAAUGCAGAACCUCCAGGGCUCCCCAGGACUCGGGAUGCUGGAGGCUGGGAAAUCACACCCUCCUGGCUAAGUCACAAGCCUCAGCGUCCCCAUAAAUACCUGCAGCUCAGCUCUGCUCCUGGGGCUGGUGGGACCAGGCAAUCUGCAUGAGGCCAUGGGUCUGUGUGGCCAUGUCACCAUGACAGGGGACAUUGACAUUGAGGUCACAGGGAACGAGUGCCACCCUCAAACACGGCCCCUCUCUCCCACCUCACCCCUCAGUUGAUUUCAUCCUCGAUGGAGGUCUCAGUGGCCUUCAAUACACUGAUGAGGCUCCAUCAACUCCUUCUGGGGGAGGUCCCUCCCCAAACCUCAAGCCCUUUCCGCAGGCUCCUUGGACCUCCCAGGCGGUGGUCGCCUACCCCUAUCAGCUCACACCGCCCUAGACUCCUCCCUCUCCCUCCCACCCAGGUGUCUCUCAGAUGACACCCUCCAAACCCUGUCCCUCCCUCCUGCUCAGGUCAGCGAGACCUCCAUCCCUCUGAGUCUCCCUGCCUCCAGCCUCACUCCCCUUCCAUGGGAAUACCAGCCUGGAUCUUCUUUCUCCCUGGAUCUUUGAGAGCUCAUUUCCCUACAAGUGCAGACCCACCUUCAGCAGGGCACACACGGCUGGCCAGGACAAGGCUCCACUGCUGACCACCCUAUCUUUGCACUCCCAGAUUUCCUUUCAACAUUCUUCUCCUCCCUCACUCCCACUGCCCAAAAUGCCCUUUCUCCCUUCCACCCAUUCUCCUUGUCAUCCCUCAGCCGUCAUCUCCUCCAGGUCACACGUUUCAGUCCCCCAUCUCAGGACACAUCAUCUCCCCUCUGUCCCCAGAAUUGGCCUCAUUUAAUGCACUUUCCAUCCCAGUCAUCACCCAUCCACUCAGCCAGGGAAGAAGUGUCCCCUGCCACACAUCAGGCCCUUUCCCAGAGCCGGGCACCCAGUGGAAAACAAGGCAGGUGACGGCCCUGCUUCCCUGAAGUUCACAUCCAAGGUGAAGAGGGGGUUGCAAAGCUCAAGAAAAUUGUAAUAGUGAUGAGAACCACAAGGACCACCCAACAGGGAAAUGUGAUCAGGCGGGACUGGCUUGAGGUGCCACAUUGGUCAGGUGGUCCCAGAAGGCAUCUGAGGAGACAACAUCUCCCCUGAGUCCUGAAGAACCUGAGGCAGCCACCAGGUGAAGGUCUGGGGCAGGGAAUGCGGCAUGAUGAGAAAGGAUUUGUUGUGUUGGAGAAAUGGCCAGUGCAGCUGGAACAAGGGGCAGCAGGGAAGGAGGUCACGUCAGAAAACGAGGCAAGUGCCAGGUCACGCAGGACCUUGCAGAAAGGUGGAUCCUUUCCAUGUGCAGUGAAAAAUCCUGGGAGGGGAUGAGCAGGACUUACGAGGUCACACUUUCCCUGUUGGAAUAGAGCAACGGGGGCGGCAGUAGAGGCAGGAAGACCAACUGGGAGUCCCUGUGGCCGUCCAGGUAGACACCGUGGCCUUGUCACAGUGCAGCCCUGGAGAGACACGAGGGAGACAGAGGCUGGGGCAGCACUGACAGCACCUGCUGUUGAAUUGAAUAUGGGGAGAGGAUGUGGAGAGAAGGGGAAUCAAAAUGAUCUCAUCACAUUUGGGCUGGAGCAGCUGGCUGGAUGUGAUGCCACUGCUGAGAAGGUGAAGCCUGGGGAGGAGCAGGUUUAGGGCAAAGAUCCAGAGUCCCAUGCUGGCCUGGAUAAGUUUCCCACAUCCAAGACAUCCAUUAGCUAUCCAGGAGGACGGGACACAGGGGGUGUGAGACGCUCUAGUUUGGAGCUCAUGGAAUAGUUGGGCCUGGAGACAAAAACAUGUAAAUUUCAGCAUUUCAAUGGAAUUUAAAUCUGUGGAGCUAAAGAAAAUAAUGCAGAUCAUGCUACUUAUUCAGUCUCAAUUAAAACUCAGCUUGUAGCAAUCAAAGAUGGAGAGUUUCAACCAGAAGUAAAUGAAAAGAAUUAGAAAUGCCCUGAGAAAUUUGGACAAACAUGUUAUUGAUAUAAAUACUUUGAGAUGCAAAAGCAUUUCACAUGUGUUUGAAAGAAUAAGGAAAAUGUUAGAAAAUAAUUGUCACUGAAGAUGAGUCUACCCAUGAUCUGUCAGUUGUCCUGAAAUUGAGUAAUUUCUUAAAAUGACAAUGUCCUGUGAGUUUACUUUAACUAAAAUGCUUACGACUCUGUUAUUCUUAAUGAUAUGUGAUGAUCUCUGUAUUGUUGGUAUAAGGAAUUAUAUUCCCUACUUGUAUGUUUCAUAGAA